AUCUCUGUUGGUUGCUCGGCCAGGCUCCACGUCAAAUCCAGUUUGAAACACAGACCCUAGGACCACGCAGGAGGUGGUGGGCUCGCAGGAAGGUUCCUCUCCCAGUGGCCAUGGGUAGCAACAGUGGGCAGGCUGGCCGCCACAUCUAUAAAUCCCUAGCUGAUGAUGGCCCCUUUGACUCUGUGGAGCCGCCUAAAAGACCCACCAGCAGACUCAUCAUGCACAGCAUGGCCAUGUUCGGAAGAGAGUUCUGCUACGCGGUGGAGGCAGCGUAUGUGACCCCAGUCCUGCUCAGCGUAGGUCUGCCCAGCAGCCUGUACAGCAUUGUGUGGUUCCUCAGCCCCAUCCUGGGAUUCCUGCUGCAGCCCGUGGUCGGAUCGGCCAGCGACCACUGCCGGUCCAGGUGGGGCCGCCGGAGACCCUACAUCCUCACCCUGGGAGUCAUGAUGCUCGUGGGCAUGGCUCUGUACCUCAAUGGGGCUACUGUUGUAGCAGCUUUGAUUGCUAACCCAAGGAGGAAGCUGGUUUGGGCCAUAAGUGUCACCAUGAUAGGUGUCGUUCUCUUUGAUUUUGCUGCCGACUUCAUUGAUGGGCCCAUCAAAGCCUACUUAUUUGAUGUCUGCUCCCAUCAGGACAAGGAGAAGGGCCUCCACUACCAUGCCCUCUUCACAGGUUUUGGAGGUGCCCUGGGUUACCUUUUGGGUGCUAUAGACUGGGCCCAUCUGGAGCUGGGAAGACUGUUGGGUACAGAAUUCCAGGUCAUGUUCUUCUUCUCUGCAUUGGUGCUCACUUUGUGUUUUACUGUUCAUCUGUGCAGUAUCUCUGAAGCCCCACUUACAGAGGUUGCAAAGGGCAUUCCCCCACAGCAAACCCCUCAGGACCCUCCAUUGUCAUCAGAUGGAAUGUACGAGUAUGGUUCUAUCGAGAAAGUUAAAAAUGGUUACGUAAAUCCAGAGCUGGCAAUGCAGGGAGCAAAAAACAAAAAUCAUGCUGAACAGACUCGCAGGGCAAUGACAUUAAAGUCACUGCUGAGAGCACUGGUGAACAUGCCUCCUCACUACCGCUACCUUUGCAUCAGCCACCUCAUUGGAUGGACAGCCUUCCUGUCCAACAUGCUGUUCUUCACAGAUUUCAUGGGCCAGAUUGUGUACCGCGGGGAUCCCUAUAGUGCACACAACUCCACAGAGUUUCUCAUCUACGAAAGAGGAGUCGAGGUUGGAUGUUGGGGCUUGUGCAUCAACUCCGUGUUUUCCUCACUUUAUUCUUACUUUCAGAAAGUUUUGGUAUCCUACAUUGGAUUAAAGGGUCUUUACUUCACGGGAUAUUUGCUGUUUGGCCUGGGGACGGGAUUUAUUGGGCUCUUCCCGAAUGUCUACUCCACCCUGGUCCUGUGCAGCCUGUUUGGUGUAAUGUCCAGCACCCUGUACACUGUGCCCUUUAACCUCAUUACUGAGUACCACCGCGAGGAAGAAAAGGAGGUGUGCUGUCAUUGAACCUCUGCCUUGGGUAACAUCCAGACUCAUCUGAAGGCUGGGGAGGAUUUGGUAGCAAUGUGUAGAGCAGAGCUGGAAAAUAAGGGUUCUUGAAACAGCAACAGUCAAAUGCCCAACCAACUGCAACCAUGAUCUGGUACAGGCAUGCUCACCAGCCCAGCCCAGCCCAGCUGUCCUGUCCUCCUUAUUCUCAACUCCUGCUCACUUAGGGAGCUGUAGGGCAAGAAGUGUUACUCCCAUUUUUCUAAUUAGAAAAAGGCUUGGUGAGGCUGAGAAACCAGCCCACAAUUACACAAAGACAAAAAAAGGGGGACCCAGGUCUUCUGUAACCACCUCAUAGGUCUCCCUGGUGCCACCUGCAGCAUUUCUAGAUACCGACAAUAAGGGUCUCCCUAUCCCCAACUUUCAGAGGUACAUAGUGGAAUUUCUUGGCAUUAUUUGCUGAGGGUAGGAAAGUCCUAGGCAAUGGAGUCCAGAUUUUAGUAAGUCAGACCCCAUGUGUGAGAAGGAAAGCUGGAAUCAUGGGUGGUAAUCCCCACUUUGCUGCCCUGAGCGGGACCUGUGCCAUUUAAACCUUGGAACGCAACUAGUGAACAAGCGCCUAUGCAGUGCUUAUAACAGAGUUGGUGUUUCCACUCUAAAAUUACCACCUCUUCUUAUCAAAAUUUGCAACUUUCUUCCUGUGAAAAUAGGCUUAUAGUUCCUUAACUGGAGCAAUGAUAUAAAAGCUACAGAGAUAACUCCAAGUUUAAUCCAGCUCAGCAUGAAACUGCAAAAACACUGAACAUAUAACCAUCAGACUAUAAUUCUGGCCAUGUUUUUCAUCAUUUGAUCUGGCAGCAGGGCAGAGGUGCACCAGGAGUAAAAACCUUUCAAAAAAGAGGUGUGGCUUUCCUCAUCCCCUGGCAAACAUUGUCACCAAGGUGGGAUGUUGCUGCUAAUGGGAGAGUCAUCAUAAAAAACUGUCCCUACAAGGAGAGUGUUACAUGGUGUUGGGGGAAGAAAACCUACGCUUCAGGCUCAGAGAAACCUGGAUUCAAAUCCUGCCUCUCUCACUUGGAAGCUGUGUUACACUGGGGAUGUUAUUUACUUGUUUAUUAGUUAGCACUUAGAAUGAGUUCAUUUUUAGGUGAGAUAAUAUAUUCACAAUGAUACACAAAAGUGCACACUGUGUGCUCCCUUUACCAUUUACUAUCUCCCUCCAGCCCCAACGUGUUACCACUCUUACUAGUUUUUUGUUAAUCUUUCCGGCAUUUUUAAAUAAAAACCAAGCAAAUGUAAA